AUUUCCUUUCUCCACAUCCAGGUCAGGUGGCGUUUGCUGUGGCGGCUAGGCCCGCGUGCGCUGGAGACCUCCGCGCUGGCCCCCGCGAGCCUCCUGCCCUGGCCCGGCGCUGCGGCUCUGCCGCGGCGGCAGCAUGGGUGGCCCCCGGGGCGCGGGCUGGGUGGCGGCGGGCCUGCUGCUCGGCGCGGGCGCCUGCUACUGCAUUUACAGGCUGACCCGGGGUCGGCGGCGGGGCGACCGCGAGCUCGGGAUACGCUCUUCGAAGUCCGCAGGUGCCCUGGAAGAAGGGACGUCAGAGGGUCAGUUGUGCGGGCGCUCGGCCCGGCCUCAGACGGGAGGUACCUGGGAGUCACAGUGGUCCAAGACCUCGCAGCCUGAUGAGAAAACUGAGACCCCCAAAAAUAAAGACUUAACUGAUGGUUCAUAUGAUGAUGUUCUAAAUGCUGAACAACUUCAGAAACUCCUUUACCUGCUGGAGUCAACGGAGGAUCCUGUAAUUAUUGAAAGAGCUUUGAUUACUUUGGGUAACAAUGCAGCCUUUUCAGUUAACCAAAUCCCUAUGAAGUUGGUCACUGGCAUCACAUUCGUAAGUAUAUCUAAUCAACGUUUACCAUUUCAUGGCCUUUUAAAUUAUUUAAAAUUCAGCAGUGCUUCAGUAAAACAAUGAAUGCAUCUAACAUUUAAGUACAUACUUUAAAUUGUAUAUCGGUCUUAUGAAUAUGAUUCUGAUGCUGAUGGUCCCUGGACCACACUCUGAUAACCACUAAUCAAUGUAAAUGGCUCCUGCAAAUGGAGACUUAACACUAAGACUAAAGAGCUUAAUUUGAACAUGUGCUUCUUCCUACUCUUCCUCACAACCCUCCAGCAUGAAAAAAUAGUUAAAACAAAAUUUCGUAAUUGUUUUCAGCCAAUGCCCUUUGUUAACAUUGUCAUAAGUACAAAAUUAUUUUGAAUUUAUAGUUUUUUUUAGCCCAGCUUUCUCCAGAAUGGCAAGGUUUACUGUAAAGCUCUAUAAACGUAUAGGGAGAUAGAGAAUCUUUGUGCAUUAUGUACUCUUUCAGUUAUAAAUGACAGAAUUCACUUUAAAUUAUUUUAAGCCUAAAAGGGAAAAUAUUGAGCUCAGCUAACUUGGACAGCGAAGAAUAGCAUUGAUUUCAGGCACAACUGAGUCCAGUUCAAGGUUGCAGAGUUCCCAGAGUUCUCUCUUUCUCUACCUUUUGGCUUUGCUUAUGGCCGCUCAAUUUUAUGUAUUGGUCUUUAUCUUUCUGGCCACAAAGUGGUUUUCUUCACCAGGGUUGAAAGAAAGCCACUAGCCUCUCUAAGCCUUCAUCUCUGUAGCUCAUUAUCCAAAAGGUACAGUUGUUCUUCUAGGAUCCAGUGUUAACCCUUUGGAUCAAUCUCCGGGGCAAUUUCUGGAUCAGUCGAGGGACCAUGGCCCAUGUUUAUUGAGGCCUGGUUCACAUGAGCAUCCUGCAGCUAAGUAGCAGGGAUGGCUGUGAAUACAAGUGAACAACAAUCCCAGCAGGGACCGUGUGGGACAGAGGAGAUGCCACAUCUGCCCCCGUGGAAAGAGAGCCACUAGACAAGCAAAAACAAUAGCUAGUGAUUAAUGUGUUAGCCUGCCUUUAAAGAAGUAUUUCUGAUGGCAUAAUUUUGUAUUCCUCUAAAAUAAGUUGUAGUCAGAGUAGGCCAGUACCCACUGGAGAAGAAGUACUUUCUUGAGCAGCGGGGGUCAGUGCCCUCACCAUCAAUUAUAGUACCUUAAUCUGCUUUAACAAUACAGUUAAAAAAAAAAAAAACUUUUCUAGUAACUGCAAGUCCUUCGAAAGAACUUGAAAUUGUAAAGGGAAAGUUUAUUUCUCUUUUAAUGCUAAGAUCACCCUUAACGGUAAAAUGGAGUAUUGAGCUAUUUCUAAGAAGUAGAUUUUGGCAGUCUUUUUCUUUUUUCCUGCUAGAAUAGCAUGUCUUCACUUGACAAGAAUAAUUUUUAGCAUAUUUUUCUUACGAGAAUUAAAGCGAUUUAAUUCUUUCAAUGUUUGAGCCAAAAGCACAUGGUAACAUAGUAUUGCAACCAACUGUAAGACAUCCCAGAUUAUUUUCCCUCUGAAUAUUUGGGUACCAUUUCUCUUCUUUUUUUUUUUUUUUUUUUUCUUUUUUUUGUGGCAGAGUCUCACUCUGUUGCACGGGCUGGAGUGCAGUGGUGCAGUCUCAACUCACUGUAACCUCCUCCCAGGUUCAAGCGAUUCUCCUGCCUUAACCUCCCCAGUAGCUGGGAUUACAGGCACUGGCCACCACGCCUGGCUAAUUUUUGUAUUUUUAGUAGAGAUGGGGUUUCACCAUGUUGGCCAGGCUGGUCUCUACCUCCUCACCUCAAGUGUUCCACUCAUCUCGGCCUCCCAAAGUGCUGGGAUUACAGGUGUGAGCCACUGCGCCUGGCCCUGGGUACCAUUUUUCAAACUGUGUGGAACCUGAUUCUGCAAGAUAUCAGUGCGUUCCCACCACUUCCACUGCUGAAAAAAUGACCCUUUUUUUGUGUUUAGUUCAUAGACAUACUAUCGUCAACACACCCCUCUUCAAGAUUCCCAAUGCACAUGGACAUAUUAAAGAAACAUGCUUACUCUUGUUAUACUCAGAUUUUCCUAAACUUAGAUAACCAUGGGAAACCACCCCCCCUUAUUUUUAUGGAACAUCUCUUAACAUUUUGAGGGAUUAGUGUUUCAAAUAAUACGUGUUAGCAAAACACUACUUUAGUAUUCUAAAUCCAAAACACUAACUUUAGUAUUCUAAAUUAUAACACUUUUCCAGUUUUGCCUAUAAUGGAGAAGUCAUAUAACUCAUCUCAAAGAAAAAUAAUUUUAUUUGUAAGUUGCUUCAAGAUCGUUAUAGUAUCUCUAUAAAUUUUUAUUGUAUUUCUCAACAUUGUAGUUUAAAUAAUUAUAUAUCUUAAUAAUCUUAUUUUCAAUGGAUUUUCUUUACCUAUAAAAGUAUGGGUAGUGAGAUUUUUUUAAAAUAUGAAUUAAAUAUUUGUAUAUGGGAAAGAGAUUUCCAAAAAGCCGUUGAUUUUUAAUUGUAUUUGUGGAUGCAAAGAAUUCAGUGAACGGAGAUGCAUACUGAAGUCCCAGUCCUGCUUUUUUUUUUUUUUUCCCCUCGUAGGCUAUUAUUCGUGAAUUGGGUGGUAUUCCAAUUGUUGCAAACAAAAUCAACCAUUCCAACCAGAGUAUUAAA